AUUCACUUAUUCGAAUGCUUGCUGAGUUCUGUGUUGCUACUGGUUUAGUUCUUGGGAUACUGCGAGUGAACAGUGGGCGGCGAGGCUGUUGUUGCAACGUCAGAGUAAAAGAAGGACCCUGCACGGCGGCCUCCCAGCACUUCGGGAGGCCGAGGCGGGCGGAUCACCUGAAGUCAGGAGUUCGAGACCAGCCUGGCCAACACGGCGAAACCCCGUCUCUACUAAAAAUACAAAAAUUAGUCGUGCAUGGUAGCGCGCGCCUGUAGUCCCACCUACUCGGGAGGCUGAGACACGACAAUCACUUGAACCCGGGAGGCGGAGGCGGAGGUUGCAGUGAGCCGAGAUCCUGCCGCACUGCACUCCAGCCUGGCGACAUAGCGAGACUCCGUCUCAAAAUGAAAAAAAAAGAGAAGUUCAUAGUAUAUUAGUGAUAAGUGCUGUGGUGGAAAAAAAAAAGUUCAUAGUAUAUUAGUAUAAGUGCUGUGGUGAAAAAAAAAAAAAGCGAAUUUCAUAGUAUAUUAGUGAUAAGUGCUGUGGGAGAAGGAAAUAGGAAUGUCCUAGGGCUGAAGGGCUAAAGCAGUUCUGUGUAGGAUUGUCAGAGACUUAUUUUUGAGCUCGCUGUAAGACUGAGAAAUCACGUAGUCCUUCCUGAAACCACUAAGAGGAAAAAUGUCUGUGACACUGCAUACAGAUGUAGGUGAUAUUAAAAUUGAAGUCUUCUGUGAGAGGACACCCAAAACAUGUGAGAUGGAGUCUCGCUGUGUCCCCCAGGCUGGAGUACAAUGGCGCGAUCUCGGCUCACUGCAACCUCCGCCUCCUGGGUUCAAGCAAGUCUUCUGCCUCAGCCUCCCGAGAACUGGAAGAGGAGGCAACAGUAUUUGGGGCAAGAAGUUUGAGGAUGAAUACAGUGAAUAUCUUAAGCACAAUGUUAGAGGUGUUGUAUCUAUGGCUAAUAAUGGCCCGAACACCAAUGGAUCUCAGUUCUUCAUCACCUAUGGCAAACAGCCACAUUUGGACAUGAAAUACACCGUAUUUGGAAAGGUAAUAGAUGGUCUGGAAACUCUAGAUGAGUUGGAGAAGUUGCCAGUAAAUGAGAAGACAUACCGACCUCUUAAUGAUGUACACAUUAAGGACAUAACUAUUCAUGCCAACCCAUUUGCUCAGUAGCUAUGAUAGACCUGGACAAAUAACUUGACAAAUUGCUGGAACACACUUAUUGUGGUUUACCCGGUUUUAAUUAUGUCAGAGAUUGCAUCAUCCUUCUGCUUGUUUACAACUAUGAUCUUCUAUGAAAUGGUGGUACCAAGGGGCGCCCAACAGCUUUUAUCCCCAUUCUUAGAGCAUAUUCUUUAUUAUAAUGAUUAUCCAACAUAUUUCUUUAAUUUUAAUACAAAAAAUACAUCAUUUAAUUUUUGUUACAUAUGAACAUUCAUUUUUAAAUGCUCAGCCUCAAGUGCAGGCAUUUUUGAGUGGCCUGAUUACAUAUUCCUCCCACAGCAAGUCCGUAUCCUGGAAGUGUUAUUUUAUAAUAAAAUUUAAAAAGUUUUAAAGAAUUAAAUCGUAGGACAAAUUAAUUAAAAUAUUGUGUAAAAUUACCUUCAGGCUAUGUGUAUAAGGUAUAUAUGAAACGUAAAUGAACUUCAUGUUUAAAUUUG